AGAACUGCGUCUCGCGACCCAGGCGCGGGUUUCCGGAGGACAGCCAACAAGCGAUGCUGCCGCCGCCGUUUCCUGAUUGGUUGUGGGUGGCUACCUCUUCGUUCUGAUUGGCCGCUAGUGAGCAAGAUGCUGAGCAAGGGUCUGAAGCGGAAACGGGAGGAGGAGGAGGAGAAGGAACCUCUGGCAGUCGACUCCUGGUGGCUAGAUCCUGGCCACACAGCGGUGGCACAGGCACCCCCGGCCGUGGCCUCUAGCUCCCUCUUUGACCUCUCAGUGCUCAAGCUCCACCACAGCCUGCAGCAGAGUGAGCCGGACCUGCGGCACCUGGUGCUGGUCGUGAACACUCUGCGGCGCAUCCAGGCGUCCAUGGCACCCGCGGCUGCCCUGCCACCUGUGCCUAGCCCACCUGCAGCCCCCAGUGUGGCUGACAACUUACUGGCAAGCUCGGACGCUGCCCUUUCAGCCUCCAUGGCCAGCCUCCUGGAGGACCUCAGCCACAUUGAGGGCCUGAGUCAGGCUCCCCAACCCUUGGCAGACGAGGGGCCACCAGGCCGUAGCAUCGGGGGAGCAGCGCCCAGCCUGGGUGCCUUGGACCUGCUGGGCCCAGCCACUGGCUGUCUACUGGACGAUGGGCUUGAGGGCCUGUUUGAGGAUAUUGACACCUCUAUGUAUGACAAUGAACUUUGGGCACCAGCCUCUGAGGGCCUCAAACCAGGCCCUGAGGAUGGGCCGGGCAAGGAGGAAGCUCCGGAGCUGGACGAGGCCGAAUUGGACUACCUCAUGGAUGUGCUGGUGGGCACACAGGCACUGGAGCGACCGCCGGGGCCAGGGCGCUGAGCCCUCGUGCUGGAAUGGUUGUCUGGUAUCUGAACUGAGCCUGCUGGCUGGACCAACUGUCCUCGAAAAGACACAGCUGGCUUCCCUAGUACAGAGAACAGGGCUUGGGCCACUUUGGAGAGACAGAAUCUAGUCCUGGGCAACUUCACAUCCGUCCUCCUGUCUCAGGGCUGGCAGGGGGAGCCUGGAAUUACCCCCUAGUGAUGGAAUGACAGGGUCUGGUGGGGACUGAAUUCCCUGGCCCUGGGGUCAUAGCUUGGGCUGUUCCUUCUCUGAUACGGGAAGAGACCCCAAUCAGAUUUUUCAAAUUAAAGCCAGUCCUGGGAAAUCUCAAAUCCGUGUGCUGCUUUGUCUCUGGGCAAAUGUGAAGGCGAGAUAAAAACAUCAAACAUUUUAUUGGGCGUAGGCUGUGUACGAGGCACAGUUUCUAAGCACGUCACUGUGUUAACUCAUUUAAUCCUAUAACAGCCCUACAAGAUCGGUAGUAUUAUCAUCCCUAUUUUACAGGUGAGAAAACCAAGGUUCCAAGAUUAUCACUUGAGGUGGGUUUUAAAUUAUGAACUUUUUUUUUUUUUUUUUUGAGAUAGGGUCUCGCUCUGUCACCCAGGUUGAAGUACAGUGGUCUGAUCAUGGCUCACUACAGCCUCAAACUCCUGGGCUCAAGCGAUCCUCCUACCAGGCCACUUUUUUUUUUUCUUUCUUUUUUUUUUAAGACAGAUUCUUACUCUGUCGCCCAGGCUGGAGUGCAGUGGCGUGACUUCGGCUCACUGCAACCUCCACCUCCCAGGUUCAAACGAUUCUCCUGCCUCGGCCUCCCAAUUAGCUGGGACCGACUAAUUUUUUAUAUUUUUUGUAGAGACAGGGUUUCACCGUGUUAGCCAGGAUGGUCUUCAUCUUCUGACCUCGUGAUCUGCCUGCCUCAGCCUCCCAAAGUGCUGGGAUUACAGGCGUGAGCCACUGUGCCUGGCCUUUUUUUUUUUUUCUUAAAUUUUAUUUCUUUUCUUUGCUAGCAGGAAGUCAAGGCAACUUUUUAAAAAUGAAAGCAAGUCCUCGCCUGGAGUCUACCUGUAUUUAUUGAGGAGCGAAGGGGAGAUUGCUUUCAGAAUGGUCCCGAAAUAAAAACACAAAACCUGGACCCUGGACAGAUCCUCUCCAAGGAGCCCUGAGAGUCGGCUCUCCAGGAAAAUGGGGGAGGAAAGGGGGACAACAGCCCAUUUUUAAAAAUAAAAUUCACUCCUGGUCUUAAA